UCCCACCACCACCCUGUCCUCUAAGAGGAAAAGAAGCGGAAUCGUGUGUGUGUGUGUGUGUGUGUGUGUGUGUGUGUUUGAGUGUGAGUGUGCAUGCAUGUGUGUUUGUACCUUUUUUUUCUGGUUAGAAAUAGAUUUUAUAUCUGUUGCAGGGAAUUUAAAAACUAUGUAGACAUAUAAGAAGGAAAGUAAAAAGAGUCCAGUACCGUCCCUUCAGAGAGCAGUGUUGCUGAUAUUCUUGGCGUUCUUUCUCUCCUCUUUUCUGGGUAUGGGGGUGCAUGUGUGCCAGAGAACACAGGGCUCACACGGACAAAUGUUUCUUUCACUAACAUGACAUCUUCAGCAUUUUGCCUUUUGACAUUUUUGGGAAAUAAUUUUUUUUUGUUUUAGUUUCUGUUUAUUAUUUAUUUCAUUCUAUGAUUACACAUUAAUUAUUUAAUCACUCAUCUAUUGUUAGAUAUUUGGGUUGUUUCUAAUUUUUUUUUACUAUUUUAAAUGGCACCACCAUAAGCAUGUUUCUAUCAAAAGUCUUGUUCUUAUUUCCUGAAGGGAGAUUCUUAGAAGUGGCCUCCAUGUGUUCUCCAUAGCCUAGUCCCACCUCUUCCCAGAGUACCAGCCGUUUCCUUGCUUCAUCUCGUCUCUUUGCCUUGGCUCCCAUCCUUCUCCCCUUGGCCUAACCCAGUUAAGGUGGCCUCAAGUGCGAUGCUACUGAUCACUCUCCAGCCCCAUAGUGCACUUGUUCUCAUGGUCAAACAAUCCGUCGUGCCAUCAUCUGUGUCUAUUUGGAAAGCAUUCCUGUCUCCAAGAGGGUACACACUCAGUGACCAACAAAUAUUUAGUAUGCAAGUGACAACCUGAGUUUUCCUGAGGGACCUCUCCCUUAAAACAUAUUCAUAUUCUGGAAAUCCUUCAACAGUACAUGUAAAAACAGUGAGUCAAGUUGAUUAUGUAGCAGCUGACUCUCAGCUAUGAAAUCUGGGACAAAGCUGAGAGCUGAGACCCUUUCUGAGGGCAUGGGAAUCAGGAUUGACCUUGUAAGCGCUUAGACUGUAUCUAUUAAACUAGUAUUGACCAAGGGCCUACUCUGUGCUAGGAACUGAAAUGGACAAGUGAACCAGACAGGCCAUGUGUCUUGGGGUAGGUGGGGGAGGAGAAUGGGGGAUAGAUAAUAAAUGCAAGCAUAACAAGUAAUGCAUCAUAAACUACAUUUAGAUGCCAGAUGCUAUUGGAGGAGAAGUGCAGAGAAAUAAGGGGCAUCAGUGUGUGGGGGAAGGUCAGUCUGCUUUAUUAAUUGGGGGUGGAUGGAAGAAGAGUUGUCAAGUCUGAUGCCACAGUUUGGGCCCUGAGUAUCCACAGGAGGCCAAGGCUGUCAGCCCAGCCGGAAGAGGCUGUGGUGGAGCAGCUGGCUGGGAGCUGGGCUUGGGACAGACAGGGUUUGAGAUGCUUAUCAUCAUCCAAGAAGAAAUGCUAAGUAGGCAGUAGGCUAAGUGAGUCCAGAAUUGGGGAGCAAGGUCCGGGCAAGAACCAAACACCGGGCAAUCGUUAGUGUAUAGACUGUAUUCAAAGCAAUGAGACUAGGUGGGCUUACCAGGAGAGUGAGUGUAGACCAGCACAAUAAGUAUAGGCAGAGAAGAGGAGCAAGGGGCUUGGCCAUGGACCUCAGGGGGCACGUGGCAGAGGCAGCCUCUAACCCACCCAAUCAACUUCCUCCCAUGCUGGGCUAUUUCCACUGCCCCCUGAUGCCCACACUCACUGGCCUGGAGUAUGGAGUCCAGGACACAAUAGCUUCCUGCUGGAGCCUAGAGGCUAUUGAGACCAGCCCAGUGCAACCCCAUGCCUGGUACCAGCCUCAGGGCUGGGUUUCUCCUCUUUAUUAUCUUUUAUUGUGCCUCCUCCCACCCUCCCUUCCUUUCCUCCUUCCUUCUUUCUUCCUCUGUCCUCCUUCUCUCCUUCCUCUUGUUGUCCAUCCCCUCCUCUCUGCAAAGAGACUUUUCCACUUGAUGUUUCCUCCAUCUGAAAUUCUCUCCCUGAAUCCUCACUUCCUCUGAUCUCUGCUCAGGUAUCAUCUUCUCAAAGAUGGCCCUCCUGGCCUCCCCCUUUCUAAAAAAGCGCAUCUUCCAACUCUUCUCUUCUAAUCUCUAUGUCUCUAUCCUGACUCUUUCUCUUCCUAACAUCCAUCACACCUGUCAUUACACCUUAUUUUUGCUUGAUUUUUCUAGAAUGUGAGCGGGACCUUCAUUUUCUUUGCUGCCUGGAACAGUGCCUCAUUCAUAGUAGGUUUUCAACAAAUACUGUUGAUGAGUGAAUGACUUCAAAGGGCUGUGGGAAGUUCAGCUGUGUCCUUAGAGCUGACCCUCAGCAUUCCCCUUUGCAGUCAUUUCACACCUUCCCAGGUGAUAGGCGGUCAGCAAAGCUGCCACAGGGCUGCGAGCUGUCCUGCGGCAGAUGGGGUGCUCCAGUGGACUCUGGGCUGUCGCCAGUGGGCCCUCACCAGAACUAGAGGGUGUGAAGUGCAGAAAGAAUUCCAUGUGAGGAGAUGCCCCAGCAUGAUACGAGGGGGCCUGUGCAGCUCAAAGGAGCAAUGUGUCCUCUUGGCCCCCAGGAUAAAUUAACUGAAAGCCUGCACUCAGGGAGGCAGGGGUCACGGUCCAUAAGGACGCUAGGCUGCAGGGUCUGAAUAGGGUUUCUACUGGGCUGGCACCUGGAGUCCAGGUUCCCCAUUUGGUCAGUUGUGUGGUCCCAUCCAUGCUGCUGCCUCCUGUGCCAACCCCCACCAACACACACACACACACACACACACACACACACACACACACACACGUCAAAACCAAAGCCUCCAAGGGCCACGCAUUGCCCUCCCCUGACCUUGGGAAGCAGCCACUUUUACAUCCUCUUUACAGGAGUUCAGGCUGAAGCUUGUGGGGUUCAGGAGACCAUCCAGGGUCAUGGGGAAGGUAAACAGGGGGCUGGGCACACCCACUACAGCCAAAGCCCUGGCACAUUUCCCUGCCAAGCCGCUUCUCUGAGACCCAGUUUCCUAAUCUGCGGGAGGAGAGGAGCUGUGAGGAGAAGACAAAAUAACACCUGUCUGGCAAUAGCAGCGCUUAAAACACAUUGGGUGGAAUGGAAUCACUGCUCACCUCAUGAGCUUCAAAGGGGCCAGGUCUGCCUUUGGUUCUUUGACUUUUGCUUCUCUUGAGGUUGGUUUGUGUGUUUUGAACAUAGGGUGGAUGAACAAGGCAUUUCUAGUCUGUUAAACUAAUCAUCUUAAUAUUUUAUUUUAAUUGUAAGGUGCUUAUUCCCUUUUGUUCCUUUAACAAAUCCAAUUAAAACAGAGUACAUCCAGAAUUACAAAAUAGAUGCUAUUAAACCAAUAAGAAAGCAUAAUCUUUUGUUAUUGGGCCGUGUGACCUCUUGGGAACUUUUGCUCCAAAUAAAAGUUGAAUUCUUAUUAUCCGCUAGGGGAAAGAGGGCAGUUUGACAGCUAACGGCUUUCCAGGCAGCACAUGUGCAGAGCCACGCUGGUGCGAAGGAUAGAGAAGUAAAUAAUACUAGGGGCAGACAAAGCUAUAAAUGCAUAAUAUCCCAGUAAGACACUUAGAGCUUGGUUGAUCAAAUUAACCAGAUAAUUGCCAAAUGAAGUGAACCUGAGAAUUUUUAUACAGACACUCCAUUUGCUACUUUACAGGCAUGUGGGUGGAAGUUUUGACGUAAUGGGAAGAACGCAUCCCACAGAAGUGCUGGAAUAAGGCAGCUGUGUGAGCCUGGACAAACUUCUCACACAUAUUCCCCUCCCCCCACCACCCACAAUAGGAGGGAUAUUCCUACCACAAAGGAGAGUGUUGCGGAUGACUGAAAUGGCAAAGGAGAGGUCACUUUAUGAAGACACGGGCAUGAUGUACCUCUUAGCAUGGGUCUGAGGAUGUGUGUGGAAGCAGGGGGGAGGGUUCGGGGGAGGCAUCAUUUGACCAGCACAUAGAGACGGCUGCUGUUUGGCAACAGCAGAAGUACUUAACGAGAGGUUAGACUUUCAAGUGAGCUCACACGGUAAAAAUCAAACUUCAGGCAGUCUGCAUACAGCCGCCCCUGAUACAGGGGCACUACAGCAGCCUGCAGCUCUCCAGGGCAAAGAGGUCACUGCCUCUCUGGUGAGAACCAGAGAAUGCAGUUGGCCAAUGUCCCUGGGCAAUGCUACAUGAAAAUCCUGUGUCUUCACACUCUUGACUCACACUCCAUGUGGCAAGGCGUUCACACUGCGUUGGGCCUGCAGGGACUGGAGAAGCUGAGAAACAACGAGUUCCUGCCUCCAUUGCCACCUACUUGGGGACACAUGCCUAUGAAGUGAACUGGCUCGUGGCAUUAUGUGUGCCCCAUAAACUGUUUCUCUUUCUCUCUUUCAUUGUCAAUUACCAAGCUCUUACAGUUAAAUGACUCCAUUAAUGCUAUUAAAAUAUCAUUAACAUUCAUACUAUUUGUAUAUAUUUAGAAAUAUACCCACAUAUAUAUGGUACAUCUAUGAAAAUGAACAUCCUACAUAUUGGCCCCUGGACAGUGGAGUGAGCAGACAAUGGGUCACACUGAAAUGAUUUCUUCAGGGACCUUAUUUGCCUGUGGUCAGUUCCUCCAAAAGCAGUUUUUCAUGAUUUUUCCUCACACUGAUCACUAUCCAAUCAGAACAAUAAACUUCUAACACUCCCUUACUAAAAGAACAUGGUUAAGGGUGAGAAAGGCCCCAAGGGCAAGAAGAUCACCCUCAAGGUGGCCAGGAAUUGCAUCAAAAUCACUUUUGAUGGGAAAAAGCGCCUUGACUUGAGCAAGAUGGGAAUUACCACCUUCCCCAAGUGUAUUCUGCGCCUUAGUGACAUGGACGAGCUGGACCUUAGCCGGAAUCUUAUCAGGAAGAUCCCUGACUCCAUCUCCAAGUUCCAGAACCUCCGGUGGCUGGACCUGCACAGCAACUACAUAGACAAGCUGCCUGAGUCCAUUGGCCAGAUGACCAGCCUGCUCUACCUCAACGUCAGCAACAACCGGCUGACCAGCAACGGGCUGCCCGUGGAGCUGAAGCAACUCAAGAACAUCCGCGCUGUGAACCUAGGCUUGAACCACCUGGACAGCGUGCCCACCACACUGGGGGCCCUGAAGGAGCUCCACGAGGUAGGGCUCCAUGACAACCUACUGAACAACAUCCCCGUGAGCAUCUCCAAGCUCCCCAAGCUGAAAAAGCUCAACAUAAAGCGGAACCCCUUUCCAAAGCCAGGUGAGUCGGAAAUAUUCAUAGACUCCAUCAGGAGGCUGGAGAACUUGUAUGUUGUGGAGGAGAAGGAUCUGUGUGCGGCUUGCCUGAGAAAAUGCCAAAACGCCCGGGACAACCUGAAUAGAAUCAAGAACAUGGCCACGACGACACCGAGAAAGACCAUCUUUCCCAAUCUGAUCUCACCCAAUUCCAUGGCCAAGGACUCCUGGGAAGACUGGAGAAUACGCUUGACAUCUUCCUAGAGUAGCUGUGGCAAAAUCUUGAAGACUACUCAGCUAACAGAAUAAACGACUCUGAAGAGGAGAAGCCCCCAGUUAGGAGAAGACAGAGUGGCAAGUGAGAUGUUCUGGAAACCAGGCUCGCCGGAGCUGGCCAAGCCACCGACUUGCUUCUCAAAUUCACUUCACCUCCCUUAGCUUUAGCCCACCUGUGUGUGAAAAUGACUUUGGGAAAUAUUUGAUGUGGUUUUUAAAAUGUAUAUAGAAAAAAAUUUAAGAAAAUUACAGAUUAUAUAUUAUAGACAACUAAAUAUUUAAGACUUUAAGACUUAAAAGGCUUACUGCCUCUACAUUUCACUCAGACUAGUACAUCUCAAUGCCAGUAGUCUGUGAUAAAUUUAUGUAGGUAUAAUGAGAUACUGAUAUGGUUUGGGCAUUUGUCUCCUCCAAACCUCAUGUUGAGAUUUGAUCCCCAGUGUUGGAGGUGGGGCCUAAUGGAAGGUCAUGGGGGUGGGUCCCUCAUGAAUGGCCUGGUGCCAUCCUUUUGGUAAUGAGUGAGUUCUCACUGUAUUAGAUCCUGUUGAAAAUUGAUUGUUAAAAAGACCUUGGCACCUCCCUCUCCUCUCUCUCUCUUCCUCUCACUAUGUGAUGCCUGCUCCCCUUCACCUUCCACCAUGAGUGGAAGCACCUAUACCCCAAAGCCCUCACCAGAAGGAGGUGCCGGCACCUGUACAGCUUGUAAGAACCAUGACUCAAAUAAACUUCUUUUCUUUAUAAAUUA